CUCAGCGUCUCCGGGUGGCGGGGCGCGCGGGAUGGAGGAGUCUUGGGAGGCUGCGCCCGGAGGCCAAGCCGGGGCAGAGCUCCCAAUGGAGCCCGUGGGAAGCCUGGUCCCCACGCUGGAGCAGCCGCAGGUGCCCGCGAAGGUGCGACAACCUGAAGGUCCCGAAAGCAGCCCAAGUCCGGCCGGGGCCGUGGAGAAGGCGGCGGGCGCAGGCCUGGAGCCCUCGAGCAAGAAAAAGCCGCCUUCGCCUCGCCCCGGGUCCCCGCGCGUGCCGCCGCUCAGCCUGGGCUACGGGGUCUGCCCCGAGCCGCCGUCACCGGGCCCUGCCUUGGUCAAGCUGCCCCGGAAUGGCGAGGCGCCCGGGGCUGAGCCUGCGCCCAGCGCCUGGGCGCCCAUGGAGCUGCAGGUAGAUGUGCGCGUGAAGCCCGUGGGCGCGGCCGGUGGCAGCAGCACGCCAUCGCCCAGGCCCUCCACGCGCUUCCUCAAGGUGCCGGUGCCCGAGUCCCCUGCCUUCUCCCGCCACGCGGACCCGGCGCACCAGCUCCUGCUGCGCGCACCAUCCCAGGGCGGCACGUGGGGCCGCCGCUCGCCGCUGGCUGCAGCCCGGACGGAGAGCGGCUGCGACGCAGAGGGCCGGGCCAGCCCCGCGGAAGGAAGCGCCGGCUCCCCGGGCUCCCCCACGUGCUGCCGCUGCAAGGAGCUGGGGCUGGAGAAGGAGGAUGCGGCGCUGUUGCCCCGCGCGGGGUUGGACGGCGACGAGAAGCUGCCCCGGGCCGUAACGCUUACGGGGCUACCCAUGUACGUGAAGUCCCUGUACUGGGCCCUGGCGUUCAUGGCUGUGCUCCUGGCAGUCUCUGGGGUUGUCAUUGUGGUCCUGGCCUCAAGAGCAGGAGCCAGAUGCCAGCAGUGCCCCCCAGGCUGGGUGUUGUCCGAGGAGCACUGUUACUACUUCUCUGCAGAAGCGCAGGCCUGGGAAGCCAGCCAGGCUUUCUGCUCAGCCUACCACGCUACCCUCCCCCUGCUAAGCCACACCCAGGACUUCCUGGGCAGAUACCCAGUCUCCAGGCACUCCUGGGUGGGGGCCUGGCGAGGCCCCCAGGGCUGGCACUGGAUCGACGAGGCCCCACUCCCGCCCCAGCUACUCCCUGAGGACGGCGAGGACAAUCUGGAUAUCAACUGUGGGGCCCUGGAGGAAGGCACGCUGGUGGCUGCAAACUGCAGCACUCCAAGACCCUGGGUCUGUGCCAAGGGGACCCAGUGAUCUGGGCUCUGCCUGGUCCUCAGCCUGCCAGGCAGAUGCAGCACCCCCUACAGGGGAGGCCAGUUGAGAGCUUGGGCAGCCUCUUCCUGGACCCAGUUAUCCAGGUCUUCAUGCUCUGCUCAAGGGGGCCACAUGAGCGAGCCUAGGAGCUGGACUUCAACCCAGGAAGAUGCAUCCGAGGGAAAGGAGAUUUUCUAUGGCCUCAGGCCUGAGUGCCAAUAUUAGUCUCCAGCUUCUGUGGAUGAUCGGUUUGAUGACAUUGGGAUGGUUGUUUAGCAUUUCUGUGCCUUGGUUUCAUUAAAAUGACAAUUUCCCCCUAGAGGAAAAAGACAGGGUUAACAACCACAGCGGAUUCCAAUCUGGGUUCUCAUUCCGGCUCAUGGAAAUGAGUCUGCCGUUGUUCAGUGGCAGUGGGACUUGGCAGGGAUAACGUCAUUGCUGUGAAUUCUACUUCAGGCAGCUGGGUGUACAUCGGACACAGCCUACCGGCAGCCUCUGGAAAAUUAACCAAGGAAAAGGAGCGGUCAGCCCUGGAAAGAGGGGAGAGCAAGGUUUUCCUUCCCCACCCUGAGAGUUGGCAAAGGGUUGGCAGACAGGAAGGUUCUGGGUGGAGAUCCCGCAUGUGGGCUGGCCAGCCCCUGGCACGCUGAUGCCCAAGGGUGAGACAAGGCAGAGAGGACAGGGCCACCUGGCAGGAGAAGCCAGGAGAGCACCCCAGCUUGGUAGGUGGAAGCUGAGGAGUCUGAGUGAAAAAGGAAAUCAGAGAAAUGCAGGCACGUUCCAGGCAGCUCUUCUACCCACAGCUGCAGAGACGACCAACCUGAAGAUGUCUCCAUGCUGGGGUGCAGUGAAGACCUUCAGGCUGGAGGAUGUGGCUGACAGAGUUGUGUAGUUCCU